GGGGCCGCGGCCGCCCGGGUGCCCAACCGAACGCACGUGCGCCAGCGGGGCCCGAGCAGAAGGGGAGCCCCGGCUCUCACGAAGAAAAUGGAGGGCGACCCACGGGUUAGGGGUCAGGAAAGGCGUGGGGCGCAUUAUGCCCUGGGAGGGGAAAGCACGGAACAAGAGGCUCUGAGGGACGGAGAGGAAGGAGGGCGACCCACGAGCUAGGUAAGGCGGGCCAACCCAGGUCUCGGAAGGAAGGGGGCGGGGCAGGACGGGGCGGGAGGGGCCGCGCAGUAGCUGGGCUGUGAGGACGGUUGGCGAGUUCAUUCCGGGCUCGGGUCGGGAAGUGUCCGCCCCUGGAGUCAAGCUGGGGAGGGUGAGAGGUUGAAGGGCAAUGACUUAGGUUCCCAGCUUCUGGCCCUGCCAGGCUCUGCAGUAGCCCAAGCCCACCGCUGCCCGGUUUCUUCUCAGAGAGCAAGCCCUCGCCCUUCGUGAGCGCCAAAUCCCCGCGCUCGGCCCCGCCCAUCCACUGAGGGGUGUGGGUAGGGGCGUGGCCCGUUCCCUUGCUGGUCGGCGCCCGGAAGGCGUCCGCGUCAGCCGGAGCUCGACGCGGUGACGGUGUGCGUCGACGUAAGUGACGCGCAAGCCUGGGCCGCUCCUCCUUCCCUCAGUGAGUGCCGGCCCGGUCGGGGCGGGGGAGAAGAGGGAGGGCGGGGGAGGGAGAGGCGACCCGAGAGUCGUUGUGGGUCGCGGGCCGGACCGGGUCCCGGGGCGGUGGGAGCCCCGGCCGGGCAGAAGGGCUUGGCGGGCCGUUAGAGGACCGCCACGGCUGUCGAGUCCCCUCCCUUGUUGGACUUGCGCGCCCUGGCGCUCGGAACCUCCGGCGCUGUGCCCACCCCGCUCUAGCUCGCGUCUCCCGACUCCAAUUAGGUCAGGCUCGGAGUCCCGCGGCCGCGGCUCCGGUCUCAACGCUCCGGGGCCGCUCGGCUCGCCUUUCUUCCCUCGCCUUUCUCUCCUCUUGCUUCACCCUCCCCCCUUCUUUUCACGUUGCUGGUUUUUUUUGUUGUUGUUUUAUGCUUUAGGGGUUUUGUUCCUCGGCUCGAGCUCAUGGGUGUACAUUAUCAUGCUCUUCUUUUGUAGAGCAGCCCGACGGCCAUGGAGGCUGAAGAGACGAUGGAAUGCCUUCAGGAGUUCCCUGAACAUCAUAAAAUGAUCCUCGACCGAUUGAAUGAACAGCGAGAGCAGGACCGGUUUACUGACAUCACCCUAAUUGUCGACGGACACCAUUUUAAGGCUCACAAGGCUGUUUUGGCUGCUUGUAGUAAGUUCUUCUACAAAUUCUUUCAGGAGUUUACCCAAGAACCAUUGGUGGAGAUAGAAGGUGUUAGUAAAAUGGCCUUUCGCCAUUUAAUUGAGUUCACAUAUACAGCAAAAUUAAUGAUACAAGGAGAAGAAGAAGCCAAUGAUGUAUGGAAAGCAGCAGAGUUUCUACAAAUGCUAGAAGCUAUCAAAGCCCUUGAAGUCAGGAACAAAGAAAACUCAGCUCCCUUAGAGGAAAAUACCACAGGAAAAAAUGAGGCCAAAAAAAGGAAGAUUGCAGAAACUUCAAAUGUUAUCACUGAGUCAUUGCCAUCUGCAGAAUCAGAACCUGUUGAAAUUGAGGUAGAGAUUGCCGAAGGCACCAUUGAAGUGGAAGAUGAAGGCAUCGAAACAUUAGAGGAAGUGGCUUCUGCCAAGCAGUCCGUAAAGUACAUACAGAGCACAGGUUCCUCUGAUGAUUCUGCUCUAGCACUGUUGGCAGAUAUUACCAGCAAGUACCGUCAAGGUGACAGAAAAGGGCAGAUUAAAGAAGAUGGCUGUCCAUCUGACCCCACGAGCAAACAGGAGCACAUGAAAUCACACUCCACUGAGAGUUUCAAGUGUGAAAUAUGCAAUAAACGAUAUCUUCGAGAGAGCGCAUGGAAACAGCACCUAAAUUGUUACCACCUUGAAGAAGGUGGAGUCAGUAAGAAGCAAAGAACUGGGAAAAAAAUUCAUGUAUGUCAGUACUGUGAGAAACAGUUUGACCAUUUUGGACAUUUUAAAGAACAUCUUCGAAAACAUACAGGUGAAAAACCUUUUGAAUGUCCAAAUUGUCAUGAACGAUUUGCUAGAAAUAGCACUCUGAAAUGUCACCUCACUGCAUGCCAAACUGGAGUAGGGGCAAAAAAAGGAAGGAAGAAGCUCUACGAAUGCCAGGUCUGCAACAGUGUGUUUAACAGCUGGGACCAGUUCAAAGAUCACUUGGUAAUACACACUGGAGAUAAACCCAACCAUUGUACUUUAUGUGAUUUGUGGUUUAUGCAAGGAAAUGAAUUAAGGAGGCAUCUCAGUGAUGCUCACAAUAUUUCAGAGCGUCUAGUAACGGAAGAAGUUCUUUCAGUAGAAACACGUGUGCAAACUGAACCUGUAACAUCAAUGACUAUUAUAGAACAAGUUGGGAAGGUGCAUGUGCUACCAUUGCUUCAGGUUCAGGUGGAUUCAGCACAAGUGACUGUGGAACAAGUCCAUCCAGAUCUGCUCCAGGACAGCCAGGUGCACGAUUCACACAUGAGUGAGCUUCCAGAGCAGGUCCAAGUGAGUUAUCUAGAAGUGGGCCGAAUUCAGACUGAAGAAGGUACUGAAGUACAUGUAGAGGAGCUGCAUGUUGAACGGGUCAAUCAAAUGCCAGUGGAAGUACAAACUGAACUUCUAGAAGCAGAUUUGGACCACGUGACCCCAGAAAUCAUGAACCAAGAGGAGAGAGAGUCUAGCCAAGCAGAUGCUGCUGAGGCUGCCAGGGAAGAUCACGAAGAUGCUGAGGAUUUAGAGACCAAGCCAACAGUGGAUUCUGAAGCAGAAAAGGCAGAGAAUGAGGACAGAACAGCUCUGCCAGUUUUAGAAUGAAAUUACACAUGAAUAUAUUUUUAAAUUUACUUGUUGGGUUUUUGAACUGAUUAUGGGCAGUUUGACUGUCCUUAAUUAAGCCUAACAGACAAGUGGACCAAAGUUAAGCUGUUUCCUGUUGUGCUGAACUGUUGUCCGUUGAAACACAUUGAUUCCCCUCCCCCUACUUAUUGCCACAGAGGAGGGAUCUUUUCCAUAACUGAAGGGGAGUUUUGAGAAGUAUAUUUCUGGAAACUUAAAUGGAUUAUAUUCUUAUUAUAUAGUUGGGUACGAAUGUAUCUAUUUUCAUUGUGGUAAAAGUUCUUCCUUUUCUCUUUCCCAGGUCAUGUUCUUCCUCAAAUUUUUUCCAUAUUGUAAAAUCAAACUUAAAUCAUUAGAAUACAAGUUUAUGUAUUCUAAUGCAUGUUAGAAAAUUGAAUAAUAUAGGAAACACAAGGCUGCAUGAUGAAAAGUGCAUUGUUACUGUGCAGUUAAAUUUUGGCUUCUGGCUUUCUUUAGUUUGAACAAACGUUCUUGUCUACCCCAGUAGUCACAGAUGCCAUCUUUGCAACAGAAAGAGUGGUGGUGGCAAAAUUUCUAGAAUGUUAAAAAAAAAAAAAAAUCCACACCCAUGUGCCUUCUCAAAACCAACUGAACUUCUAUAAAGCAUCUCUGGUUCUUUCAAAGUUUGUGUUGUAAGGAGCAAUGUAGAUGAUGCUAUAAUACUUUAUAUUUUUGGUUAUAAUGACAACCACCAGUUCUUUUUCACUUAAGUUAGGUUGAGAAAUUUUAUUUAAUGGCCACUGAAGGGCCAUUUUCAAUUGGGAAAAUUUAUUUACAUCUGUGGUAAACUUUAUUUUGAUGAAAAGUUGCACUAGUAUUUUACCACCAGAUGAGAAAAAGAUGAGCAGCAUUUAAAAAUUAAUGUAUUUAAAAUAAAGUACAGAGAAAGACAUGUAUAUAAUUAUCAGGCUUUGUUUUGAAUGGAAUCUUUUCCCCCAAUUCUUAAUGUAAAGAUCUUGUGCUAUAACUUUUAAAGCCAUACAAAUAAGAGUGCUAAACUGUGGACUUAAAAGUAGGUGUGUAAAUAUUUUUAAUCAGUAUUACUUGGAAAAUAAAAUAUAACAAACCCAUAGACCAAUAUGCUAUUUUUUUUACCUGUUAAAUAUUGGGAGUUCUUUACAUUUUUUAAGUAAACUUUAAAAUUAUG